GGAGCUGAAGGAGGAGCUUGAUGGAAGCGUGCGAGAAGGGGCGUAACUGAUUUGGAAACCAGAGGAAAGGCGCUGUUUUCACCGAAUUAGAAUCGCGGGAAAAUAGAGAAGAGUUUGUUUGAAGGUCUCGCGAGAUCGAGUGAGUACGGCUCGCCAAGUUGGAGCGCUCUCGCGAUAGACACAGCAACUAUUCAGCUGCGAGGGGACGGGAGAGGUGGUGAGCACUCUCGCGAGAUUUGAAGGAGCGGCGGAGGCCAGAGGGAGGAGAGGUUUGUAAACUAGGAGGCUCCGGGUUUCCGGGCACUUUUAUUAGGUCGUCUUCUGGGCCACCAGUGCCCCUUCCAUCUCCACAGGCAGUCCCUCCAUCGCUAACCUUUUUUUAACCGGCCUUUUAGGACCGGAAGUCCUUCAUCUCAAGCAUCCAAUGCUGAAAGCGGCCUGAUUUUCUCUACCGGAAGCCCUUUUCCAGAGGCUGGGAACACGGCCCACCUAGCAGGAAGUCCCACCUCCUUGAGCUCCGCCACCCUUCCCGAAGUUUUUCUGUCACCUGUGUUAGGCUCCGUCCCCUUUCCGCGUUUUAUCCCCGUACCAGAAAAGGAUACAUUUAGUGCCUCCCACCCAGCUCCACUAAACGGGUUGGAUAUCUCAUUCUUUGAGUUGGUGUUCCUUCCCCGGCGCCCCCAUGUAGCUGGGAAGUGGGACCUGGGGGUGGUUGGACCCCUGGGAUCCUAAAGGAGGGGCAGGGAGGGCGCAGAACUCCGCUUCUGCUCCUUGCUACCAGGACGCGCGGCCUCCUCAGCCUCUUUCCUCCCGCUGCCAUGCACCCUGCAGCCUUCCCGCUUCCUGUGGUUGUGGCCGCUGUGCUGUGGGGAGCGGCCCCGACCCGGGGGCUCAUUCGAGCGACCUCGGACCACAAUGCCAGCAUGGACUUUGCAGACCUUCCAGCUCUGUUUGGGGCUACCUUGAGCCAGGAGGGCCUCCAGGGGUUCCUUGUGGAGGCUCACCCAGACAAUGCCUGCAGCCCCAUUGCCCCACCACCCCCAGCCCCGGUCAAUGGGUCAGUCUUUAUUGCGCUGCUUCGAAGAUUCGACUGCAACUUUGACCUCAAGGUCCUAAAUGCCCAGAAGGCUGGAUAUGGUGCCGCUGUAGUACACAAUGUGAAUUCCAAUGAACUUCUGAACAUGGUGUGGAAUAGUGAGGAAAUCCAGCAGCAGAUCUGGAUCCCGUCUGUAUUUAUUGGGGAGAGAAGCUCCGAGUACCUGCGUGCCCUCUUUGUCUACGAGAAGGGGGCUCGGGUGCUUCUGGUUCCAGACAAUACCUUCCCCUUGGGCUAUUACCUCAUCCCUUUCACAGGGAUUGUGGGACUGCUGGUUUUGGCCAUGGGAGCAGUAAUGAUAGCUCGUUGUAUCCAGCACCGGAAACGGCUCCAGCGGAAUCGACUUACCAAAGAGCAACUGAAACAGAUUCCUACACAUGACUAUCAGAAGGGAGACCAGUAUGAUGUCUGUGCCAUUUGCCUGGAUGAAUAUGAGGAUGGGGACAAGCUGCGGGUACUCCCCUGUGCUCAUGCCUACCACAGCCGCUGCGUGGACCCCUGGCUCACUCAGACCCGGAAGACCUGCCCCAUUUGCAAGCAGCCUGUUCAUCGGGGUCCUGGGGACGAAGACCAAGAGGAAGAAACUCAAGGGCAAGAGGAGGGUGAUGAAGGGGAGCCAAGGGACCACCCUGCCUCAGAAAGGACCCCACUUUUGGGUUCUAGCCCCACUCUUCCCACCUCCUUUGGUUCCUUAGCCCCAGCUCCCCUUGUUUUUCCUGGGCCUUCAACAGAUCCCCCACUGUCCCCUCCCUCUUCCCCUGUUAUCCUGGUCUAAUAACCCCCCACACAUACACCUCUGGUGACCUAUUUGCACAGACCGUCGUCUUCCCUCCAGUCUUCUGAGGGAUAGGGGACAUUCCAUCCCAAGCUUCUCCCUUACCCACACCUAUCCUUUUGAGGGGCUUUGGGGUGGAGCUGGGGCAAGCAGAGGGACUGGGUCUUCACUUCUUGGGCUAAUAAAAUUGUUUCUUUGUGGACUAA